GCGCUGCGGCCGCCCGCGCGGACCCGGCGAGAGGCGGCGGCGGGAGCGGCGGUGAUGGACGGGUCCGGGGAGCAGCCCAGAGGCGGGGGGCCCACCAGCUCUGAGCAGAUCAUGAAGACAGGGGCCCUUUUGCUUCAGGGUUUCAUCCAGGAUCGAGCAGGGCGAAUGGGGGGGGAGGCACCCGAGCUGGCCCUGGACCCGGUGCCUCAGGAUGCGUCCACCAAGAAGCUGAGCGAGUGUCUCAAGCGCAUCGGGGACGAACUGGACAGUAACAUGGAGCUGCAGAGGAUGAUUGCCGCCGUGGACACAGACUCCCCCCGAGAGGUCUUUUUCCGAGUGGCAGCUGACAUGUUUUCUGACGGCAACUUCAACUGGGGCCGGGUUGUCGCCCUUUUCUACUUUGCCAGCAAACUGGUGCUCAAGGCCCUGUGCACCAAGGUGCCGGAACUGAUCAGAACCAUCAUGGGCUGGACAUUGGACUUCCUCCGGGAGCGGCUGUUGGGCUGGAUCCAAGACCAGGGUGGUUGGGUGAGACUCCUCAAGCCUCCUCACCCCCACCACCGCGCCCUCACCACCGCCCCUGCCCCACCGUCCCUGCCCCCCGCCACUCCUCUGGGACCCUGGGCCUUCUGGAGCAGGUCACAGUGGUGCCCUCUCCCCAUCUUCAGAUCAUCAGAUGUGGUCUAUAAUGCGUUUUCCUUACGUGUCUGAUCAAUCCCCGAUUCAUCUACCCUGCUGACCUCCCAGUGACCCCUGACCUCACUGUGACCUUGACUUGAUUAGUGCCUUCUGCCCUCCCUGGAGCCUCCACUGCCUCUGGAAUUGCUCAAGUUCAUUGAUGACCCUCUGACCCUAGCUCUUUCCUUUUUUUUUUUUUCCCCACUGAGAAGGGGUCUCGCUAUGUUGCCCAGGUUGGUCUCGAACUCCUGGCCUCAAGCGAUCCUCCCGCCUCAGCCUCUCAAAGUGCUGGGAUUACAGGUGUGAGCCACCAUGCCUGGCCUGAGUCCAGCUCUUUAAUGCCCGUUCAUCUCAGUCCCCUGCCCGCAAUCCUGCCUUCUGGCCUCCUCCGUCCCUGAUCCCGCCUCUGCCUGCCCAGGGGCUGCCCCUGGCCGAGUCACUGAAGCGACUGAUGUCCCUGUCUCCAGGACGGCCUCCUCUCCUACUUUGGGACGCCCACGUGGCAGACCGUGACCAUCUUUGUGGCGGGAGUGCUCACCGCCUCACUCACCAUCUGGAAGAAGAUGGGCUGAGGCCCCCAGCUGCCUUGGACUGUGUUUUUCCUCCAUAAAUUAUGGCAUUUUUCUGGGAGGGGUGGGGAUUGGGGGACGUGGGCAUUUUUCUUACUUUUGUAAUUAUUGGGGGGUGUGGGGAAGAGUGGUCUUGAGGGGGUAAUAAACCUCCUUCGGGACACA